GAGACCCUAGCUCUGCUCUCGGUCCGCUCGCUGUCCGCUAGCCCGCUGCGAUGUUGCGCGCUGCCGCCCGCUUCGGGCCCCGCCUGGGCCGCCGCCUCUUGUCAGCCGCCGCCACCCAGGCCGUGCCUGCCCCCAACCAGCAGCCCGAGGUCUUCUGCAACCAGAUUUUCAUAAACAAUGAAUGGCACGAUGCCGUCAGCAGGAAAACAUUCCCCACCGUCAAUCCGUCCACUGGAGAGGUCAUCUGUCAGGUAGCUGAAGGGGACAAGGAAGAUGUGGACAAGGCAGUGAAGGCCGCCCGGGCCGCCUUCCAGCUGGGCUCACCUUGGCGCCGCAUGGACGCAUCACACAGGGGCCGGCUGCUGAACCGCCUGGCCGAUCUGAUCGAGCGGGACCGGACCUACCUGGCGGCCUUGGAGACCCUGGACAAUGGCAAGCCCUAUGUCAUCUCCUACCUGGUGGAUUUGGACAUGGUCCUCAAAUGUCUCCGGUAUUAUGCCGGCUGGGCUGAUAAGUACCACGGGAAAACCAUCCCCAUUGACGGAGACUUCUUCAGCUACACACGCCAUGAACCUGUGGGGGUGUGCGGGCAGAUCAUUCCGUGGAAUUUCCCGCUCCUGAUGCAAGCAUGGAAGCUGGGCCCAGCCUUGGCAACUGGAAACGUGGUUGUGAUGAAGGUAGCUGAGCAGACACCCCUCACCGCCCUCUAUGUGGCCAACCUGAUCAAGGAGGCUGGCUUUCCCCCUGGUGUGGUCAACAUUGUGCCUGGAUUUGGCCCCACGGCUGGGGCCGCCAUUGCCUCCCAUGAGGAUGUGGACAAAGUGGCAUUCACAGGCUCCACUGAGAUUGGCCGCGUAAUCCAGGUUGCUGCUGGGAGCAGCAACCUCAAGAGAGUGACCUUGGAGCUGGGGGGGAAGAGCCCCAACAUCAUCAUGUCAGAUGCCGAUAUGGAUUGGGCCGUGGAACAGGCCCACUUCGCCCUGUUCUUCAACCAGGGCCAGUGCUGCUGUGCCGGCUCCCGGACCUUCGUGCAGGAGGACAUCUAUGAUGAGUUUGUGGAGCGGAGCGUUGCCCGGGCCAAGUCUCGGGUGGUCGGGAACCCCUUUGAUAGCAAGACCGAGCAGGGGCCGCAGGUGGAUGAAACUCAGUUUAAGAAGAUCCUCGGCUACAUCAACACGGGGAAGCAAGAGGGGGCGAAGCUGCUGUGUGGUGGGGGCAUUGCUGCUGACCGUGGUUACUUCAUCCAGCCCACUGUGUUUGGAGAUGUGCAGGAUGGCAUGACCAUCGCCAAGGAGGAGAUCUUCGGGCCAGUGAUGCAGAUCCUGAAGUUCAAGACCAUAGAGGAGGUUGUUGGGAGAGCCAACAAUUCCACGUACGGGCUGGCCGCAGCUGUCUUCACAAAGGAUUUGGACAAGGCCAAUUACCUGUCCCAGGCCCUCCAGGCGGGCACUGUGUGGGUCAACUGCUAUGAUGUGUUUGGAGCCCAGUCACCCUUUGGUGGCUACAAGAUGUCGGGGAGUGGCCGGGAGUUGGGCGAGUACGGGCUGCAGGCAUACACUGAAGUGAAAACUGUCACAGUCAAAGUGCCUCAGAAGAACUCAUAAGAAUCAUGCAAGCUUCCUCCCUCAGCCAUUGAUGGAAAGUUCAGCAAGAUCAGCAACAAAACCAAGAAAAAUGAUCCUUGCGUGCUGAAUAUCUGAAAAGAGAAAUUUUUCCUACAAAAUCUCUUGGGUCAAGAAAGUUCUAGAAUUUGAAUUGAUAAACAUGGUGGGUUGGCUGAGGGUAAGAGUAUAUGAGGAACCUUUUAAACGACAACAAUACUGCUAGCUUUCAGGAUGAUUUUUAAAAAAUAGAUUCAAAUGUGUUAUCCUCUCUCUGAAACGCUUCCUAUAACUCGAGUUUAUAGGGGAAGAAAAAGCUAUUGUUUACAAUUAUAUCACCAUUAAGGCAACUGCUACACCCUGCUUUGUAUUCUGGGCUAAGAUUCAUUAAAAACUAGCUGCUCUUAACUUACUGGGUAACUCUUUGUCCAUCUCAAUAACCAAAGGAAGGUGGGCAUGGUGGCUCACGCCUGUAAUCCCAGCACUUUGGGAAGCCGAGGCGGGUGGAUCACUCGAGGUCAGGAGUUUGAGACCAGCCUGGCCAACGUAGUGAAACCCUGUCUCUCACUAAAAAUACACAAAUUAGGCAGUCAUGGUGGCUGGCACCUGUAAUCCCAGCUACUUGGGAGGCUGAGGCAGGAAAAUUGGUUGAACCUGGGAGGUGGAGGUUGCAGUGAGUGGAGAUCAUGCCACUGCACUCCAGCCUGGGAGUCAGAGCGAGACUCCAUCUCAAAAAAAGUAAAUAAAUGAAAUAGCCUAAGGAAAUGCUGGCAGGCAGUAAUGAUAUGGCACACUGGAUAUGAUUUCUGCCCCUCCUCUGCUGUGGGUAAACAGCUUCUGUUUCAUGCAUUUACUUUUUUAUUUUAAUUACACCAAUAAGAAUGUGCUUGAAUGUUUCAUGCAUUUAAUUUGUUUCAUGCAUUUAACUUCUGGCCUGUUUACCUGUAGCAGGCUCUGAGAUGUGCUCUAGAGACAGAACCUAAACAUGAUGCCCAAGAGAGGGGAGAGAUACUGAAUGUCCAAUGUUCUCAAAUUUUUUUUUUUUUUUUUUUUGAGACAGGGUCUUGCUCUGCCAUCCAGGCUGGAGUGCAGUGGCACGAUCAUAGCUCACUGCUGCCUCGACCUCCUGGGCUCAAAUGAUCCUCCUGCUUCAGCUUCCUGGGCUAAUGUUUGUAUUUUUUGUGGAGAUGGGACUUUGUUAUGUUGCCCAGGCUGUUUUCAAACUCCUGGACUCAAGUGAUCCUCCCGCCUUAGCCUCCUAAGGUGCUGGGAUUACAGGUGUGAGCCACUGUGCCCAAUUCAGUUCUCAGUAAAAACUUGAUCAGGCCAAAUGAAAGUGACAUGGGCCAAUUUCAUAAUAGAUUGAUUUGGAAACCAGAUGUCAAUUUACUUACUUUAAGUGAGAUCUGUAUCUUCAGUAACCAGACCUCUUGAGUCUCCCACCCAGAACACUAUCUUCCUCUAGUCAAGAUACCUGGCAAAGGCCGGGCACAGUGGCUCACGCCUAUAAUUCCAGCACUUUGGGAGGCCAAGGUGGGUGGGUCACCUGAGGUUGGGAGUUCGAGACCAGCCUGACCAACAGGGAGAAACCCCAUCUCUACUGAAAAUACAAAAAAAAAAAAAAAAACUAGCCGGGCAUGGUGGCUCAUGCCUGUAAUCCCAGCUACUCAGGAGGCUGAGGCAGGAGAAUUGCUUGAACCUGGGAGGCAGAGGUUGCAGUGAGCCAAGAUUGCUCCAUUGUACUCCAGCCUGGGCAACAAGAGAGAAACUCCGUCUCAAAAUAUAAAUAAAUAAGAAAAAGAAGAAAUGGAAGCUGGGUUCAAGAGGGCAAUCAGCAGUCUCUACCAUCAUGUGAAACACCACUCUGUGAUUUGAGUCUUGACAAUGUAUUUUCUUUUUUUUUUUCUUCUUUUUUUUUUGAGACUGAGUCUCGGUCUGUCGCCCAGGCUGGAGUGCAGUGACGUGAUCUUGGCUCACUGCAACCUCUGCCUCCUGGGUUGGAGCAAUUCUCCUGCCUCAGCCUCCUGAGUAGCUGGGAUUACAGGUGUGCGCCACCAUGCCUGGCUAAUUUUUGUAUUUUUAGUAGAGACGGGGUUUUGCCAUGUUGGCCAGGCUGGUGUUGAAGGCCUGACCUCAGGUAAUCCACCCACCUCUGCCUCCCAGAGUACUGGGAUUACAAGUGUGAGCCACCGUGCCCGGCCAACUGUAGGGACCAGCCCCACAGGGUCGGUGGGUUUUUCUCCCCAUGUGCGGAGACGAGAGAUUGUAGAAAUAAAGACACAAGACAAAGAGGUAAAAGAAAAGACAGCUGGGCUUGGGGGACCACUACCACCAAGAGGCGGAGACCGGUAGAGGCCCCGAAUGUCUGGCUGCACUGUUAUUUAUUGGAUACAAAGCAAAAGGGGCAGGGUAAAGAGUGUGAGUCAUCUCCAAUGACAGGUAAGGUCACGUGGGUCACGUGUCCACUGGACAGGGGGCCCUUCCCUGCCUGGCAGCCAAGGCAGAGAUAGACAGGGAGAGAGAGAGACAGCUUACGCCAUUAUUUCUGCGUAUCAGAGACUUUUAGUACUUUCACUAAUUUUGCUACUGUUAUCUAAAAGGCAGAGCCAGGUGUACAGGAUGGAACAUGAAGGCAGACUAGGAGCGUGACCACUGAAGCACAGCACCACAGGGAGACGGUUAGGCCUCCGGAUAACUAAUGAUUAAUGAUAUUCAUAUAUAAUCAUGUCUGUGAUCUAGAUCUAGUAUAACUCUUGUUGUUUUAUAUAUUUUAUUAUACUGGAACAGCUCGUGCCCUCGGUCUCUUGCCUCAGCACCUGGAUGGCUUGCCGCCCACAGCCAACAAUGUGUUUUCAAUAUGCUCCCCAAACUACAGCAAACUCCUCUUAACUCGGGAUUUAGGGUGAUGCCCUACUUAUGCCUAACUUUAUCACCAGCUUAACCCUCAUCUCAUUAUAUAGGAUGAUAUUACUUCUAGGAAGAUUUUCUAUGUAUGGAGGGUGCAUCAUUUAAGAGUAUUUUAGGCCAGGCACUGUGGCUCAUGCCUGUAAUCCCAGCAUUUUGGGAAGCUGAGGUGGGUGAUUUGCUUCAGCCCACGAGUUCAAGAUCAGCCUGGCCAAUAUGGUGAAACCCCAUCUCUACAAAAAAAUACAAAAAUUAGCUGAGCGUGGUGAUGUGUGCCUGUGGUCCCAGUUACUCUGGAGGCUGAUGUGGGAGGAUCACUUGAGCCCAGGAGGUCAAGGCUGCAGUGAGCUGUGAUUGCACCACUUCACUCCAGCCCAGAGUGAGACCCCAUCUCUGAAAAAAACACAAAAAACAAGAAAAGAAUACUGCAAAGAACCUUGGUAGGGGUGAAUUGGAAAAAGUAGAGAAAUGUAAUAUUUCUUUCCUGCUGUACUCACUGUAACUGUGAGAGGAUCGGCUCUUUUAACCAACAGAUAAGAAAGGAAAUAUUAGCUAUGAAGAAAUGUCUAUCAAGUUGAUUUUGACAACCUAGACACAUUAAUCUCCUUGCACUUUUAGUGACAGGAACCCAUUAGAACCUUAAGCAGCUGUCUGAAGUAAAAACAAAGCUCUCAGGUGAUGAACCACCUAAUCUCCCUGGGUAUUCGGAUGUGGGUCAGUCACAGGAGUAUUAGGUGUAAAGCCGCUGCUUCUGGGUAGAGCCUCCACUUGUGGCUGCACAGAGGGCACAGAGAGCUUUUCCUUCAGCCCGGAGAAGCUUCCUAAGUGUGGGCGCCACCUUGUGGGACAUACAUUGAACUACGACGCUAUUUCUCCAAGAAUUAACAGGACAGCCCCUCCCACCGGUGUCCUUCCAACGAUGUUGCAUACAAUUUGGCUGUACAUUUGGCAGGCAGUGUAAUGAGGGAAUCAAAGACCAGGAUCACAUACUGGAAAGAAUUGAAAACAGAGACUCCCAACAAAAACUUGUACACGGACGUUCACAGCAGCACUAUUCACGACAGCUCAGAGAUGGAAUCAACCCAAAUAUCAGUCAAUAGAUGAAUGGACAGACAAAAUGUGACAUAUCCAUGCAGUGGAAUAUUAUUUAGCCAUAAAAAGGAAGGAAGUGCUGAUGCAUGUUGCGAUGUGGAUGAACCUUGAAAACAUGAUGCUGAGUGAAAGAAGCCAGACACAAAAGGAGAAGGACUGUAUGAUUUCACUUAUAGGAAAUAUCCAGAACAGGCAAAUCUAUAUAGAGAGAAGGUCGAUUGCUGGGGGCCCUGGGAAGGGACCAAGGGGGAGUGACUUCUAAUGGUGGGGUGCCCUUUUGGGGUGAUGAAAAUGUUUUGGAACCAGAUACAGGUGGUGGUUGUACAACAUUGUGAAUUUACUAAAUGCAACCAAAUUGCUCACUUAAAAACAACAAAUUCAGGCCAGGUGCAGUGGCUCACACCCGUAAUCCCAGCACUUUGGGAGGCCGAGGUGGGCGGAUCACAUGAGGUCAAGAGUUCGAGACUAGCCUGGCCAACAUGGUGAAAUCCCAUCUCGGCCGGGCGCGGUGGCUCACGCCUGUAAUCCCAGCACUUUGGGAGGCUGAGGCGGGUGGAUCACGAGGUCAGGAGAUCGAGACCAUCCUGGCUAACACGGUGAAACCCCGUCUCUACUAAAAAUACAAAAAAUUAGCCAGGCGUGGUGGUGGGCGCCUGUAGUCCCAGCUGAUCGGGAGGCUAAGGCAGGAGAAUGGUGUGAACCCAGGAGGCGGAGCUUGCAGUGAGCCGAGAUCGCGCCACUGCACUCUAUCCUGGGUGACAGAGUGAGACUCUGUCUCCAAAAAAAAAAAAAGAAACCCCAUCUCUACCCAAAAUACAAAAAUUAGCUGGGCAUGGUGGCUGGCACCUGUAAUCCCAGCUACUCAGGAGGCUGAGGCAGGAGAAUUGGUUGAACCUGGGAGGCAGAGGUUGCAGUGAGCUAAGAUCGCACCACUGCACUCCAGCCUGGGUGACAGAACGAGACUGUCUCAAAAAAAAAAAAAAAAAAAAGUGGCCAGGUGGUGCCAUGGCUCAUGCCUGUAAUCUCAGCAUUUUGGGAUACUGAGGCGGGUGGAUUACCUGAGGCCAGGAGUUCGAGAUCAGCCUGGCCAACAUGAUGAAAACCCAUCUCUGCUAAAAAUACAAAAAAUUGGCUGGGCUUGGUAGCAUGUGCCCAGCUACUUGGGAGGCUGAGACAGGAGAAUCGCUUGAACCUGGGAGGCAGAGGUUGCGGUUAGCCAAGAUUGUGCCACUGCACUCCAUGGGUGACACAGAGAGACUCUGUCUCAAAAAAAAAAAAAAAAAAGUAAAUGCUAUGUUAUGUGAAUUUCACCUCAACUGAAAAAAACAGGGUCCCAGAGCUGGUCAGGGGAACUUGGACAAACCACACAACUUCUGAGCUUCCAUUUCCUCACAAUCUCUGCAGUCACUUCCAACUCUCAUUUGGCUUAUUCUGUGAAGGAUAAAACAGAGCUGACAUUUGUUCAUUUGUAUUGAUUUUAUUUACAUUUUUCAAAAGGAAAUAGAUGCAGAUGGUAUAGAAAGUUUCAGUGAAAUGUAAAUCUGAUGCCCAAUCCUGUGGCCCCAAGAAGUAUUAACUGUGCACCCACUACAUGCCAGGAACUGUACUUGGAGCCUUCUCAAGAGCUUCUUAACAAUAUUUUCAUUUUUUAUAUUUUUUAAUGACAGGGUCUAACUCCGUCGUCCAGGCUGGAGUGCAGUGGUGCGAUCAUAGCUCACUGCAGCCUCUACCUCCUAGGCUCAGGUGAUUCUUCUGCCUCAGCCUCCCAAAUAGCUGGUACUACAAGCAUGUGCCACCACAGUCAGCUAAUUAUUUUUGGAGAGUCAGGGUUUCACUAUGUAGCUCAGGCUGGUCUUCAGCUCCUGGCUUGAAGUGAUCCUCCUGCCUUGGCACAUAGAAGGGGUUACAAUAUACAUAUAUUAGAGUGAGAGCAUAGAUGUGAUGCCUGGCGAUAUGGCUUACUUAUGAGACAGCACCUGACCUACAGCCAUCUAUGACUCCUACUGUAUCUUCCAUGCCAGGAGUAAGGGUGAGGAUACCUGGCAAUAAUAAAAAUAAUAACCUGAGAGUCUAAUGGCUUAUUUUUUGUAGAGAUGGGGUCUCACUGUGUUGUUUAGGCUGGUCUUGAACUUCUGGGCUCAAGUGAUCCUCCCACCUCAGCCUCCUGAGUAGCUGGGAUUAUAGGCGUGCACUACCAUGCAUAUAUAUAUAUAUUUUUUUUUUUUUUUGAGAGAGAGAGAGAGAGAUGGAGUCUUGCUAUGUUGCUCAGGCUGGUCUCGAACUCCUGGCCUCAAGUCAUCCUGCUGGCUUGGCCUCUCAAGUGCUAGGAUUACAGGCAUGAGACACUGGGCACAGCCCUAAUAGCUUAUUUUUAAAGCUAUAUCAAAAUGUCAUGCACCUGAACAUUUGAAGUAACCUCUCUGAUAGUACGGAUAUUUAUCCCCUCAAAAUCUCAUGUUAAAAUGUAAUCUUCAGUGUUGGAGGUGGGGCAAGGUGUGAGGUGUUAGGAUCAUGGGGGUGGAUCCCUCAUGAAUGGCUUGGUGUCCUCCCCCAUGGUAAUGAGUUCACUCAAGAGCUGGUUGUUUAAAAGGUGACGUGGACCUAAUCCCUGUUGGACUGAACAAAAGGGGACGAACACAGCAAUAAAGAUAAAGACCAAAGAGUAUAUUUGGAAGAAGGGGUCAGGGGGCUCCUUGCUUCUAGUGAAAAAGGGCCCUGAGCUUUAGUGCCCUUUGUAUUUAUUGGGUAAAGGAGAUAGGGAGAAGGGGGGGUGGUUGUCGGUCAGCAGCUUGAUUCACAGCAGGCUCACAAGAUUGCAUUCUUUGAACAGUAGGCUCUAGAUGUCUCAGUAGAUAACCUCAAAGAGCAUGGCGCCAGGGAGUGAUUGCCCUCAGCGAACCUUCUGGCGGCUGAAGCAGAAGUGAGUUUGCCCACAUUCUGCAUUUAUGAUAAACAGUUUGCUGUUUGAUCAUAUAGCCUCAGUGGAAUGCUGAGUUGGUCACAACCCAUGGGCAUUCAGCUCUCUACAUUUCCCCCUUUCUGUUUAUGAAUUAAUUGAAAGAAUGUAAGGCCAGGCUGGGCAGCUCUCAUUUUCUGAUUGGCAGUCCAUCCAAUUUUACAGACUAUGAACAGAAGACAGAGACAAAACAACAUUAUUCCAAGGACUACAUAUAAGAUGUUAAUGUGGUGCUUUAGACAGGUCCAAGGGUUGAGGCUCUCCAGGCCUUGCUGGAAUUUGGUCUAGUCUUCUAAAGAAGGCUGAAACUCUUGAGUUUGUUUAUUUAAAUCAAGAAUUUUGUUUUGUAAUUCACCGAUAUCAAAGGUGAUGUUGGAUGUGCAAGCUCCCUGCAAAUGGGCUUUCACAAGGUCCCAUGGAUACUCACUUUGGUUAUAUUCUAAGUUGGUUACACAAAUAUGAGUGUGAUUAAAAUGAUGGUGCAAUUGCUGUUGCAAUUGCAAGCUUUGUACUUGUUCUCCUAACUGUAGAGCCGUGGAUUUCAACAAUGCCACUUCAGUUUGUAACUCAGUGUUAAUUUUAUUCUGAAGUGGCCAUGCUUGGUUGGCUAUACGCAUCCAGUUUUCCAUGUACUGAGUUGUUUGAAUAGAACUAUGCAAAGCUACAGAGGACAUCACAACGGAAGUUAUUAAUGUGACCAAGGAAACAAUAGCAAAAAUUAUCAUGCCUAAGGCUCUAUGGGCACAAUGAGUAAGUUGAGUUAGAAGAUGUUUCAUGAAGUGCAAAGCAGGUGUGGUAGCCCAAGGCUGGGACAGAUUAACAGGAAUCCAUAGCCCAGGGAUGCGACCCAAAAUUAUCAAAGUAGAGACAUUAUGUGUUUGCAAUGUGCUAUGAUUAAUGCAGUGACAUAACUGGCAAGAUUUACAGGUCAAUUGGAUAUUGUUUACCUGGAGCUGGUCCUUCUUAGUUGCCAAAAAAGACAUAAGGAUUAAAAAGACAAACCAUAAA